CUCCUCGCCGCCGCUUCCUCUCGAGAAGGCGCGGGGCGGGCUGUCCGGCCCGCAGGGCGGUCGAGGUGGGAACGGAGCAGCCCCGGGGGCCCCCUUGAGGCGGCGAGGCCGCGAAGGGCGCGGGGCUGGAGGGUAGGAGAGCGCGGGAAAGCGCCCCAGACGCCACUCGCGGCGGACGGCGGCCAGUUCCCAGGGGUUUGGAGCCGGGUGCGCAGGCGUGGGGCCUCCGGGCACGGGGCGGGCCCUUAACAGGCACCGCUGCGGGGACUGGAGUCGGCGGAGAAAACCGGGGUCCCCAGCGCUGGGGCCCGCGGCGCCAUGGCUCACGUCGGCUCCCGCAAGCGCUCGAGGAGUCGCAGCCGGUCCCGGGGACGGGGGUCGGAAAAGAGAAAGAAGAAGAGCAGGAAAGACACCUCGAGGAACUGCUCGGCCUCCACAUCCCAAGGUCGCAAGGCCAGCACGGCCCCUGGGGCGGAGGCCUCACCUUCUCCCUGCAUCACAGAGAGAAGCAAGCAGAAGGCCCGGAGGAGAACAAGAUCCAGCUCCUCCUCCUCUUCUUCCAGUUCUUCUAGCUCCUCUUCUUCCUCCUCGUCCUCCUCCUCUUCCUCCAGUGAUGGCCGGAAGAAGCGGGGGAAGUACAAGGACAAGAGGAGGAAGAAGAAGAAGAAGAGGAAGAAGCUGAAGAAGAAGGGCAAGGAGAAGGCGGAAGCACAGCAGGUGGAGGCUCUGCCGGGCCCCUCGCUGGACCAGUGGCACCGAUCAGCUGGGGAGGAAGAGGAUGGCCCAGUCCUGACGGAUGAGCAGAAGUCCCGAAUCCAGGCCAUGAAGCCCAUGACCAAGGAGGAGUGGGAUGCCCGGCAGAGCAUCAUCCGCAAGGUGGUGGACCCUGAGACGGGGCGCACCAGGCUUAUUAAGGGAGAUGGCGAGGUCCUAGAGGAAAUCGUAACCAAAGAACGACACAGAGAGAUCAACAAGCAAGCCACCCGAGGGGACUGCCUGGCCUUCCAGAUGCGAGCUGGGUUGCUUCCCUGAGGGCCCCCGCUGGCCAAGGCCUGUGGACGACGCUGGCGGCCCAGCCUGGGCAGGUUUCAGGGUGCCAGUGGGAAGCCUGAUGGGUGCUGGUGGCCUUUCCCCCGUGGAUUGGUCUCUGGCCCAGCCCAGUCUCUUCUCAGGGGCAGGGGGUGGAGGUUGGGGUCACCGGCCUGCUUGGCACCCCCAUCUGAAAGAGCAGCACUUCUCAGCUAUUAAAGGCCCCCUGGAUAGAC